AAAGGCGGGGUCUCGGCCGGCGCUGACGCAGCCAUGGCGGAGGCGGCUUUGGAAGCCGUGCGGAGCGAGUUACGAGAAUUCCCGGCCGCUGCAAGGGAGCUCUGCGUGCCUCUUGCUGUGCCCUACCUGGACAAACCCCCAACUCCGCUCCACUUCUACCGGGACUGGGUCUGCCCCAACAGGCCGUGCAUUAUCCGCAACGCUCUGCAGCACUGGCCGGCCCUCCAGAAGUGGUCCCUCCCCUAUUUCAGAGCCACAGUGGGCUCCACAGAGGUGAGUGUGGCCGUGACCCCAGAUGGUUACGCGGAUGCCGUGAGAGGGGAUCGCUUCAUGAUGCCAGCUGAGCGCCGCCUGCCCCUGAGCUUCGUGCUGGAUGUGCUGGAGGGCCGGGCCCAGCACCCUGGAGUCCUCUAUGUGCAGAAGCAGUGCUCCAACCUGCCCAGCGAGCUGCCCCAGCUGCUGCCUGAUCUGGAAUCCCAUGUGCCCUGGGCCUCCGAAGCCCUGGGAAAGAUGCCCGAUGCUGUGAACUUCUGGCUGGGGGAGGCGGCUGCAGUGACUUCUUUGCACAAGGACCACUAUGAGAACCUCUACUGCGUGGUCUCAGGAGAGAAGCAUUUCCUGUUCCAUCCGCCCAGCGACCGGCCCUUCAUCCCCUAUGAGCUGUACACGCCGGCAACCUACCAGCUAACUGAAGAGGGCACCUUUAAGGUGGUGGAUGAAGAGGCCAUGGAGAAGGUGCCCUGGAUCCCACUGGACCCCUUGGCGCCAGACCUAGCACGGUACCCUAGUUACAGUCAGGCCCAGGCCCUUCGCUGCACGGUGCGGGCCGGUGAGAUGCUCUAUCUGCCGGCUCUGUGGUUCCACCACGUCCAGCAGUCCCAGGGCUGCAUCGCAGUGAAUUUCUGGUAUGACAUGGAAUACGACCUCAAGUAUAGUUACUUCCAGCUGCUCGACUCCCUCACCAAGGCUUCAGGCCUUGACUGAUGGAGCACUGGUGAACACCACCAAGCACGCCUCGGGGGACGGAGCCAGCCCCUCCCUGGCCAGGUCAAUUCUCGAGAGAGCCUGGAGUGUGCAUGCUGGCUGCUGGCCCCGGGUCCAGCAUGGCUUGAGAUCAGCUUUGGAGGAUCUUGGAAUGUGGUCAUAAGGACUCAAGGUGCCAGGCAGGUCUGGGUGAGGGUUCUCAGGAAGUUGCCACACAGGUGAGCAGAGUGGGGAUCAGGUGCAGCGGCACCUCUCCCCAGCGCUGUGAUGUUGGGCGAGUCACUGCGUCUCGGGCAUUGGUGUCCUGUCAGUAAAGAGAUAAUAAUGGCUGUACCUCGCGGGGCUGUUGUGGGCUUGGAGAUGAUGUCUAUGAGGACCAGCAUGGAGCUGGCACACAGGACAUGUUGAAUAAAAGGUAGCUGUGA